GAGAAAGAGAGACGGAGAGAGAGAGAGACGCACAGAUGUGCACGGAGGCCACAGACACUGACAUUUGGAAUUCCUUCAGGGUAAAAGGACACCGGAAUGGGAGCUUAGAAGUGUGUUGCUAAGAUUUCCGGCUGCACGGAAUUAUUAAGUUUUUCUUAAAAAAACAAAAAAAGAAAGAAAGAAAGAAAAAGAAAAGAACCCCCUCCGCAGCGAGCCACUUAGGUGCUGCUUUCACGCCAGAGUCCCCUGUUAAGGUGGCAGCCCUUGAUAACUAAUCUCGGGCACCCAGCCGCUUCUGUAAGCUUAAGGAGACGACGAGGAGGGGCGGGGGAAGUGCGUCACCAGCGGACGGAAUAGACCUCAGCAGCGGCGUGGUGAGGACUUAGCUGGGACCUGGAAUCGUAUCCUCCUGUGUUUUUUCAGACUCCUUGGAAAUUAAGGAAUGCAAUUCUGCCACCAUGAUGGAAGGAUUGAAAAAACGUACAAGGAAGGCCUUUGGAAUACGGAAGAAAGAAAAGGACACUGAUUCUACAGGUUCACCAGAUAGAGAUGGAAUUAAGAAAAGCAAUGGGGCACCAAAUGGAUUUUAUGCGGAAAUUGAUUGGGAAAGAUAUAACUCACCUGAGCUGGAUGAAGAAGGCUACAGCAUCAGACCCGAGGAACCCGGCUCUACCAAAGGAAAGCACUUUUAUUCUUCAAGUGAAUCGGAAGAAGAAGAAGAAUCACAUAAGAAAUUUAAUAUCAAGAUUAAACCAUUGCAAUCUAAAGACAUUCUUAAGAAUGCUGCAACUGUAGAUGAAUUGAAGGCAUCAAUAGGCAACAUCGCACUUUCCCCAUCACCAGUGAGGAAAAGUCCGAGGCGCAGCCCGGGUGCAAUUAAAAGGAACUUAUCCAGUGAAGAAGUGGCAAGACCCAGGCGUUCCACACCAACUCCAGAACUUAUAAGCAAAAAGCCUCCAGAUGACACUACGGCCCUUGCUCCUCUCUUUGGCCCACCACUAGAAUCAGCUUUUGAUGAACAGAAGACAGAAGUUCUUUUAGAUCAGCCUGAGAUAUGGGGUUCAGGCCAACCAAUUAAUCCAAGCAUGGAGUCGCCAAAGUUAACAAGGCCUUUUCCCACUGGAACACCUCCACCACUGCCUCCAAAAAAUGUACCAGCUACCCCACCCCGAACAGGAUCCCCCUUAACAAUUGGACCAGGAAAUGACCAGUCAGCCACAGAGGUCAAAAUUGAAAAACUACCAUCCAUCAAUGACUUGGACAGCAUUUUUGGGCCAGUAUUGUCCCCCAAGUCUGUUGCUGUUAAUGCUGAAGAAAAGUGGGUCCAUUUUUCUGAUACAUCCCCGGAACAUGUUACUCCGGAGUUGACUCCAAGGGAAAAAGUGGUGUCCCCACCAGCUACACCAGACAACCCAGCUGACUCCCCAGCUCCAGGCCCUCUCGGCCCCCCAGGUCCCACAGGCCCCCCAGGGCCUCCUGGGCCUCCUCGCAAUGUACUAUCGCCGCUCAAUUUAGAAGAAGUCCAGAAGAAAGUCGCUGAGCAGACCUUCAUUAAAGAUGAUUACUUAGAAACAAUCUCAUCUCCUAAAGAUUUUGGGUUGGGACAAAGAGCAACUCCACCUCCCCCACCACCACCCACCUACAGGACUGUGGUUUCGUCCCCCGGACCUGGCUCGGGCCCUGGUCCGGGGACCACCAGUGGUGCAUCAUCCCCUGCUCGACCAGCCACUCCUUUGGUUCCUUGCAGAAGUACCACUCCACCUCCACCUCCUCCCCGGCCUCCAUCCCGGCCAAAGCUACCUCCAGGAAAACCUGGAGUUGGAGAUGUGUCCAGACCUUUUAGCCCUCCCAUUCAUUCUUCCAGCCCUCCUCCAAUAGCACCCUUAGCGCGGGCUGAAAGCACUUCUUCAAUAUCGUCAACCAAUUCCUUGAGCGCAGCCACCACUCCCACAGUUGAGAAUGAACAGCCUUCCCUCGUUUGGUUUGACAGAGGAAAGUUUUAUUUGACUUUUGAAGGUUCUUCCAGGGGACCCAGCCCCCUAACCAUGGGAGCUCAGGACACUCUCCCUGUUGCAGCAGCAUUUACAGAAACAGUCAAUGCCUAUUUCAAAGGAGCAGACCCAAGCAAAUGUAUCGUUAAGAUUACCGGAGAAAUGGUGUUGUCAUUUCCUGCUGGCAUCACCAGACACUUUGCCAACAACCCGUCCCCAGCUGCUCUGACUUUUCGGGUGAUAAAUUUCAGCAGGUUAGAACACGUCCUGCCAAACCCCCAACUUCUCUGCUGUGAUAAUACACAAAAUGAUGCCAAUACCAAGGAAUUCUGGGUAAACAUGCCAAAUUUGAUGACUCACCUAAAGAAAGUGUCUGAACAAAAACCCCAGGCUACAUAUUAUAACGUUGACAUGCUCAAAUAUCAGGUGUCUGCCCAGGGCAUUCAGUCCACACCUCUGAACCUGGCAGUGAAUUGGCGAUGUGAGCCUUCAAGCACUGACCUGCGCAUAGAUUACAAAUAUAAUACAGAUGCAAUGACGACUGCUGUGGCCCUCAACAAUGUGCAGUUCCUGGUCCCCAUCGACGGAGGAGUCACCAAGCUCCAGGCAGUGCUCCCACCAGCAGUCUGGAAUGCUGAACAACAGAGAAUAUUGUGGAAGAUUCCUGAUAUCUCUCAGAAGUCAGAAAAUGGAGGGGUGGGUUCUUUGUUGGCAAGAUUUCAGUUAUCUGAAGGCCCAAGCAAACCUUCUCCAUUGGUUGUGCAGUUCACAAGUGAAGGAAGCACCCUUUCUGGCUGUGACAUUGAACUUGUUGGAGCAGGGUAUCGAUUUUCACUCAUCAAGAAAAGGUUUGCUGCAGGAAAAUACUUGGCAGAUAACUAAUGAAAUCUUAUGCAAGGAUUUGGAGGAUUCAUAUAAUGGAGAACUGAUGUAUGAGAAACAGAUUUUAAUUUUGGUUUGAUGAAAACAAACCAAUAUCUGCACUUGGGAUAUAUCAGGUGGAAAGUCAAUGACUUUCAUCUGUGAUUUCCCUCACACACUACCAUGAUGACCAGUCCUACAGUAUUUACUUCUAGGUGUAAUAUUGUUAAUGGUUUUAAAAUGUAAUUAUUGUAUUUGUAAAUUGUACUCUCAUUCCAGUAAGGCAGUUAGACACUUGAGUUUUAGCAUUUUACCAUUCCUGAAAUGGAUGUAAUUUAAACUGUGGUAUGUAAAUUUAAUAGUAGUAUUGUUGAAUGGCACAAUGCUUACAGAGGUAGAUUGCAUUUUGUCAAUAUAUAAAAUUUAAAUAUAAUAUUGAUAGCUGUCAUAAAGGGGGUGCCACAUAUUAAAGAAACUUAAGUGGAACCAGAAGAAAAAGAAACAAACUUACUUUUCUUCAAUGCUUAGUAUGUUUUACUCUAGUGCUAAAUAAAAACUCUAUCUUCAAAUGUUUAGUGGGUUAAAUUGAGAAACUAUUUCAGAAAAAAAUUCUAAGGUUACAGCAUAUUCAAAGAAAAGCAUUAGUUACCACUUUUUAAAAAGCUUUUUUUUCAAACUGCAAAUUUCAUAAAAAUGCAAACUGUGUAAACAGGGCCUCUUAUUUUUAUAACUUGUGUAAAAAGGGAAAGCAAUUCAUAUUUAAAGUUUAAGUAUAUUAAAUUAUAAUCAAGAGUAAAGAAGAUGUUGAAGUCUUAACUACUUGCCCCUCUCUACAGUUUCGCAAAUGUGGGGAUUGCUGAAUAAUCAGUCAGACUAAAACCAAAAUUGUGAUUUUAAGAUUUCAAGACUUUCCGUAGUUGAACUGGUUAAGAAUUUUUGCUUAGUUACUCUGAAUAGAUGAUCUUACUCAUCCAGUAUGGGGGAAUGAUACCUCACGUCUUCCUCUUUACCCACAGGAAUCAAAACGCUGAGACUGAGAAUUUUAGGGAAAAAAAAGUCCACUGUUUAGAUCCAGAAGGAGAGUUUUAAUCAUUGUUUAUAUCAUUUGAGAAUGAAAAAAUAAGCUUCAUAAAUGAAAUUCUAUUCACAUUACUGUGUAAUAAAUUUCCUUUUGGAUGAUUAGGAUUCAUUGUAUAAAACUGUAAAUCUUUGCCAUUCUUGGAGAAGCAAAAGGAGAGUUAUCAAAAAUGUAUGUCGUUUCAUCGUUGCAAGGUAUAAUAAAAACUGUAAUUAUUCAAUCUGGCCCUGCCAUAUGAACAUUUAGAAAGACAAACUUCUUCGGGAGUCUCAGUUGUAAAACCUUCCCUCAUUAAUAUCUGAAAAUGUUAGUCUUCCUUUAAGUCAUAGAACUUAUUUAAACAUAAACCAAUUUCUAUUACAGGUUAUGCUAUUAAAUAGCUGUAAUUAUUAAGUUAUUAUUUUUAUAAUUAGUUGUUAAAUUUCAUUUUACACCCACUCAAAUUUAACAAAGAAUCUUUAGCCCCUUUAAAUUUUAGAAUUAAAUUAAAUUUUUAAAGUUUUACUUCUAAAAUGAGAUUGUGACUGGCAAUUGUUUAUAGUGAAACUUUUUAAAUUAAUCUUUGUACUCCUCUAUCAGUGCUUGCUACCAAGAGAAUGUCCAAAAUGAUUUGUUUUACCAUGGGAAAAUUCUUACUAUUCAACAAACUCUCAGUUGGCCCCCUACAGCAGUCUGGUGUUGAAGUUUCUUUGAACGAACUAAAUAUACUCAUUUUAUGUAAAGGUAUCCAAUUUGAUUUUGAAACCAAAAUAGAAAAUGCAAAAUUCUAAAUUCCAUGAAACAUGGAAUUUAUGACACCAAAAUCAAUGGAGAGUAAGCAGCAGCAAACUGAGAAUUAUCCAGCAUAUGAAUAUAACAAUGUGUUUUUAAGUAAUCAAUUCAUUUAAAAAAUUGAAUAUUAAUACAAAGCAUAUUAAAAACAUGUAAAUAUUACUGGUUCUCAUGUCUUUGUAUUUAUAUUUUAUUUUGUUUUAUUUUGUAUAGAUCUAGAAUGAAUUAGUAAUUAAACACAAGGGUUUUUUUCCCAAAAAAUAAUUUUACUGAUUUUUAAAAAUUUAAUUAAAAACAUAGAUUACAGUAAUCUCUAACAUUAUUCAAAUCUUUCUAGGGAUUAAAUUAGAAACUAUGAAGAAAUCCUAUAAUCUCUUAACUGGUCUUUAUGGAACAGAAUGGGAGUCAACAAUUUCAAAAUGAUUGAACUAUGAGUAACCAGAACCUCAAUAGAAAAUGUAUCCCUUCACCUUUCAGAAAAGAGAUCAAAUAAUAACACAAUAAGCUGGUAUCAGGGAUUUGCAUUUUGACAUUUUGUUGUUUCUUUUUAAUUUUGUAGAUUAUAAUCUCCUGUUACAUCUAUAUCCACAGUACUGUAGAAUAAGAAUUCAUGUCCUGAAAAUGGUCCCAGGCAAUGAAAGAGUCUCAGUUAUCAAAGACAUUAAGUCAGAUUCAUUUAUUCAUUUUAUUCCCAAGUCAGAACAAAAUGAACUAGUAGGUAAUAAAACUAUUUUCAGUACUAGGGGUUAAAACAAAAAGAAAUUGUUCUAGUUAACCAGAACACCAUUUCCUGAACGUUAUGAUCUUUAAAAGGUUCUGCUUUAGCAAGAUAAAAAGUAUAAAUGAUGCUACUUUAUUUUGGCAACAUGGAAAUUUUGUUUUUCUUUUCCAAUAAAAUCCAUAUUUUCGUGAAAUUUUUAAAAAUAAAUUUGUAUCAAGGAUUAGUCUGAAUUUUAUCAUAAUAGAAAUUUAUAAUUACUAAGAAUUAAAUUUUUAAUCAUUUUUAAAGCUGUGUUCUUCUCUACACCCACAGCCAAAAUGGAAAUUCACUGUAUGGUAUUUGGGAAUAUAUUUCACCUGUAAAAGAAAGAAUGUCCACAAUUCAAACGGUUUUGAGUUAAUAGAUAGGAAUCCCUCAGUCAAACUACAGAAUUUUUUUUGUUUUAUAUAUUCUUAGUCAGCAGAGUGUUUGAGCUAUAAUUACAAGUAUUUCCACUUCUAAAUCUUCUUUUAGAAAAGCAGAUAACUAUAAUACCUUGGCUCUGCCACUGACUCCUGCCGUAUGAUAUUGGACAAAUCACUGCCCUUUUCAGUUUCUCAUCUUUAGAAUGGGGAGUUGGGAUUGCCAGUGGUUUUCAAGCUUUUCUUAACAGCAGGGCUUUUUUUCUAAUAAAAUUGCACAUGGAAUCCUGGUAGGCAAAACAGCUCAAAGCAAUGCAGGAGUUUCUCCAACAGUUUAAAUUGGGGCUCCCCAGAGCAUGGUUUAAAUACCAUAACAGUACACAAUGAUCUAUCAUGUGUCUUCCAACUCUGAAGUUCCACAGUUGUAAUUUACUCAGAUAAACCACCUUUUGAGGCUUUAUAAGCAAACUUGUAAAAACACAGUAAUUGAAUGAUAUACAAUAAAAACUGACAGAGUGUUUACCAUGUACCAGUCACUAGAGAUAUUAGCUCAUUUAAUUCUCUUAUCAAUCAAAAAAUUGUAAGUACUCUUUUUAAUUCCUGUUUUACAAGUGAUGACACUGAGGCUUAAAUAGAAUAAUCUCCCCAAAAUGACACGGCAGCUGAAAGUAACCCAGCUAUUCUGACUGCAAAGGAAACGCCUUAAUUGCUUUGUCCACCCUGAACAAAACAAUCUGUUUUAUGUCACUAUACGUACUCCAUUUGAAUGCCAAGGUAGAAGGCACCAUGAAAAACCAUUACCAAAAUAAGGAUAAUUCCAAUAACAAAACUGUCAAAAAAGAAUCACUGCUUCUCAAAAUAUGAUUGGUAUCAUCACUUAUUAAUGUUUUGUAUCAUCACUUAUUAAUGAUUUUGGCUUGGUCACCACUAUGCCUGGAAGAUAGUAGGCACUGAUAAACAUUGUUAAACACCGUAACAACACAAAAUGAUCUACCACAUAUCAAUGUCUUCCAUCUCUGAAAUUCCAUGAUUCUACUUUACUCAGAUAUACCACCUUUUGUGGCAUUAUAAGGAAACAUGUAUAAUCAAGUUCAUACAAGCUAUACACAGUAGGCAUCGAUAAAUUUGUAUUGACAGCAUAAACUUCUAGGGAUGAGAUUUGGGAAUAUACAUUUUGAUAAGUGCUCCAAAUUUGAGAAUCAUUGCUCUAGUAGAUCUCUAAGGUCCUUCUUAGUUCUGACAUUAUAUCAGAUUUUAAGCAUUAAAUUCUAAGAUGAAAACCAUUUUUCUAGUCAGUUUAUUUUUCAUUCAGUCCACUUAAUUUCCUCCAAUCUUAAAAAAUUUUUUUCCCUAGGAAAAUCCCUAUCUUUUUCUUAAAGUUACUCUGUUAUACUAUCUCAGUCUCAAAGUAGCCUGAAAUGCAUUUUCUCAUUUUCAUAUUUCUGUCCUUUUCUUCAAUGUCUUAAAAGACUUGAAGUAGAAGGGAAGUUGCAAGCUGUUAUUUAUUCAAAUACAAAAUCCUAAUCAAUGUUUCCUUCUUUGCAAGGGACAUUCAGAUCUCUAACUUGUGAGUUGAACCUAUUUAUUUUGUAAGCUUUUGACUUUACAAACAUGUGGUAGCCUCAUUCUAAAAGAGUUGCACGAAUAUUUUUUCUCAAAAUAACCACAGGCUGUAAAUUAAAUUGAACAAUACAGUAGAAUAUGCAGAUACAUACUAAACAGAUGAGUGUGUGUGUAUGUGUCUGUGUUUAAGCUUUUCCUUUUCCAAAAGAUUAUACAUUUGAGCAAAAUCCCAUUCAGUCUAAAUGUACUCAUUUUGCCACAUGGUUUUCUGAUCAGCAAUUUUUUUAAAAAAUGGAAGUGUUACAUUAUAUUUAAUAAUAUCAAAACAAGAGUGAUCUCUAAAUAUAGCUUUGAAAGUUAAUAUAAUAUGAUGUGUCCAUGCAAUGAGUCAAAUUAGAUUGUUGAUAUAAAUGAACAAAUCAAUCCAAGUUACAUUGAUUAAAGGGACUAUUUGGAUGACCAGCCUCACCAUCUUUUACUGUGUGCACUUUCCUCUUAAGGUUUUAUUGUAUUUUCCCUGCUCCUUUAGGCUUUUUUUUCAUGUGGAAAACAGUAUCUAAAUGCCAUUCUCUCACUUAUGAAUUAAAUAUGGCUACCAUUAAUGUUCCUUUUUGUCAGUGGAGUGUAUGGAAGGAAAAUGAGAUAGGAGUACAUUGCUUAAGUCUCUAAAUAUUAAAAACAACAACAAAACACUUGCCUUUCUCUUGUGUCAUUGCUUCAAUGUUCUGUCAUCUUCUGCAAGCUAGAGUUGCACUGCUGACAUCUAAUUAAGAUCUAAAUAUAUUUCAUGAAGGAAUGUCAAAUGUAAAGUCUGUUGAGUUGACCAUGGUGAACCUCUUGAUUGGCCCUCACAUUUAAUAUCUGAUUUCUCUCCUAAAUGGGUAUGUCUAUGAGGAAAAGACACCUAUUUGUUGGCAUUGACCAUGGGUAUAAUAAUUUAUUCUCUAGGUUUAACUUCUAAAAUUAUUUUUCCUUUGAUUUCUAACUGCCUCCUUCUAUCCCUAGAGUAAUACCUUGCCUACCUUAAAUACAUCUUUAUCCUUGUAAAAAAUGUUUUGGCAAAAAACAAAUAUAUUUUUAAAUGUCCCGUAAUGUUUUAAAGAAAAGAAGUAAAGUGUAUUUGGGCUAUGCUCACCAAUAUUCCAGUAUUUUACAAAUUGUGUUCUGGAAGAUGUUCAUUGUGGUCUGAGAACAAAUGGUCCUAUACUAUAAUUCUCUCUCCUUGGACAUUGACAAUAAAUGUUAGUGUUUUAAUGAAGCUUAAGAAAGUUAUUGAAUCAGGUAAAAAAAAUUUUUUCUAAGCACACCUUGAGAAACCUUUGGAAAAGUUUUCUUUUAACACUAGUUUAUAUAUCCUUCAAUAAUUGUAAAUAAAAUAACCAGGAAUGCUUUGAAAAAAAUGCUUCUGGAAUUUUGUUUUAAUUUUAAGAGAAUUCCUGUCAUUUCAAAUGAAUUGUUAUCUAUUUUAAAUUUCAUUAGUAUCUCUUAGUGAAUUUAACUUUAUCAUCUAAAAUAUUCAAAACAAAACAAUAAAAUUAUUUUAAUUUUUGUAUUAUUUUUAAGGCUUGCACCUAUGACCAGCAUAUCAGACCCCUAUCUGUUGAAGAUGUUUCCAAUUCUUUGCCGUGUGGAAUUAAUGCCAGUGAAUAAUCUCCAGUAACGUUUUACUAAACAGCUUUAGGAAACUGAAUCAUGAUAGAUCAAUGUUGACAGUAUUUUUACAUCAGCUUGUCAGAAAUUAUAUUAAAAACACUUUGGGGAAAGCUAAGAGCAGUGCACUGUUUAGCACAGAUUUUGUGAGAUUCUAUACUCUUUUAAUGAGCAUUUCAUAGGGUUUUUUUUUUGCUGUUUUUUUUUCUUUUUUUGCUUUGCUUUACUUUGCCAAUCAGUUACUUUUAUACCAAAUUAACGAAGUUUCUUUAAAAACUUCCUGGUUAAAUUGUCUGUUAUCAUAUAGAAAAGAAUCAAACUGAAUCACUUUACAUUUCUCUAAAGAUAGUUCAGUUUUUAAUCCAUCCAGAGUUUGUGAAUCAGCCUGAUAGAUCAUAAGCCAUUUAUAAUUUUUAAACGUUCCAUUGAAUGAGUAUAUCAUACAAAUGUUAAUUCCAUCUCGCUCAUUCAGUUUUACAUUACUUUUAUGAAUUUUUUUUCUCGCAAAGUAAAUGCUUGAUGUUAUUCAUUCACCAUCACUCUAAGGUAUUUUAAAUCAUACAACAAGUAACUAUCACAAGAACCACUGUCCCAAGAUCCAAAGUCAGAUUUUUUUCCCUUUUCAAGUUGCUAGAAUGAUAAUUCAUAUAGCUGUGUUGAUUUUUCAGGUCAGAAUUUAGUUCUUGCUUUGUUAAAUGGACAUACAUGAAAGAGAUUGGCUCCUAUCUAAUUCAUAUUCUCUCUCUCUCUCUCUCUCUUUCUCUGUGUGUGUGUGGGGGUGUGUGUGUGUGUGUGUGUGUGUGUGUGUGUCUCUUUCCUCUCUGUCUAAGGGGAAUUGGAAAAUUGCUGCUGAAUAAUUUUUCUUGAAAAAGCCAAGUGUUGAUAUGAUGAUAUAUUAAUCUUAUCUAUGAACAGAGCUUCACCACAGGCCAAGCAGUAAUGUAUACAGCUGGCUUUUUAAGCUGUUUGAACACUAUUGUUUUCGAUUAAAAAGAGUUUUUGUUUGUUUUUCACUUGUAUAGUAAAAGAUCAUAUGAAUUAAAUACUCGGAUAUUAAUUUUCAUUCUUACUAAGUGGCCAUGUAAGGCAUUGAUUUUUUUUAAACUUGAACAAUGCAAGAAUCUAGGAAUCUCAGAAAGAUUUUGCUGUGUUUCUAUAGGUAAUGAAAUCCUGUCAAUUAAGGAAAAUGCUGUGUGUAAUUUGAUUUGGUGGUAGCCUUUAUUUAGAGCUCUCUUUGAUCUAUGUAGCAAAAAUACACUAAAUUUCUUUUUAAUCUUGUACUAAGUACAUAAUUUCACAAAAAUACCUUGGGCAUAAAAUACUUACAAAACUGUGAAUUAAAAUACUCAAGAUACUUUCAAAAUUUAGUCAAAAUGUUGAUUCCCAGCCUUUUUCCUACACGUCUAUUUCAAAAGAGUAUACUUUUUUCUGACAGCCAUUACUGCUUAGUCUGUAAUGAAAGCUUUACUGCUUCUAUGCUGUGCUCAAGAGAAAACCAACAACGGAAGCGAAGACUUACUUGCUCCUUCACAGAAUUGCAGCAAAGCUCUCUGCUGGGCAAUGGUGACAGGAAAGUGUGUAAUUGACUUGUUGAAGAUAAUCAUGAGACCAUCUUAACAUUACUUGCCUUAUAAGUUAGAAAUAGUAUGGAUAUCACUCUUUGUAAAUAAUAAUUUUUGUAAAUGUUUUUUGUUCAUAAUUUUCCCAAUCACCUAUUUCACAAAAUCCUGAAUAUGCAAUUAUUUAUUAUGACACGUUACUGCAACUAGGGCUCCCAUUCCAGAACAAAGUUUAAUUCUAUAUGUAAGUUGUUACUGAAAUGUGAUUUCUUUUUCUGGAAAAUAAAUGAAAAAUAUGAAAAUAAAUUGAAUUGUGAAUAUC